GGCCUCAGGAAGCCUCCAAUCAUGGCGGAAGGCAAGCGGAGCUGGCGCUUCACAUGGUUGAUCGAAGCUGGCAGAGGAUAGAAGAGCUCUGUGGCCGAGUGAGCUGUUUCUGGAGCCAGAUGAGUCUUUGGCAGAGCCUGAGGUCCCCUGCUACUACUGGGCCAAGACGAAUUGACAGAACUUCCAAAACACUUUGCAAAGACAGCGAGUGCACAAAGCUGCAGCUCACAGCCUUGUCCCGUGGCCGGGAGACAGGAUGCAUGCUGAGCUGCUGGGAGGAGGGACAGGAGGAAAAGUGCCUGCAGCUGCAGGAGCACCCACUUGAGAUGCCUCCUGUGUUCAAUCAAGUUCAGAGUAAUUGCUUCCUCACUCCUCCUGGCAAAACUGUUCAACUUGGCACAGUGACAGCUCCUUGUAGAGUUUUUCCAGCUGAUGUCAUUCUUCCUAAGGUCUGCUAGGGUCCCAGCUAACACGACUGUGUUGCACUGGCAUCCAGACCUCCACCAGGAGCAAUUCAAAGGCCUAUUUUUGUGAAUAUGUGGCAAAGAUCCCAGGCUCCAUGGAGGCCUUUUGCACUGGGGACAUGGUGGAAAAUUAAGCCCCAGAGGUAACUACCUACCUGAACGGCAUGAGACCAGCUGAUUAGAUGACAGAAUGGGCAGAUCCGUGGAAGGGAUUGAGUGAGCACUAACAUCGAGCAUUCUUAUAAACUAAGUGAGACUGCAAGAGUCAGGGGCCACUGUGCACAAUUGUGUGAGCUGUGUUUUGCAGCAGGUGUCUGGGGAGCUCAAAUCCACCCACAAAGGGAAGCCUUUCUGACUUGUACAAAGGGCCAUAAGUGGUGGCUCGAACCUGAGGCUCUACCAUGCAGUGAGUGUGGAGAUGUGGAGAUGGGUACACAGGAAUGGACAAUCUAGAGAGGGGAAGAGACUAACAUCCAGCAGCACGUUAACUGUGAAAGCAAACUAAAUAUGGCCUGAGAAGGACUCCAUACUUCUAUAUUUGAGUCCUCGCGGAUGGACUGUAACCUAGCUUAAUAGGCGGACAAAAUUGCAAACAUAACCUGGUAGUAUGCACCUCCAACAAUAGCUAAGUCUUGGCCAACCCCAGUGGCCAUACUCAACCAACCAUACACUGCUGAGUGUUCAAAUUAGGCAUACGCCAAGCAGUAACCAAUCCAGCUGUUUUAUACUUCACUUCUAAUUUCUGUACAUCAUUCCCCCCCCCCCACCUUUUUUUGUCUAUAAAUCUUCUCCACCUGGCUGUGCUGGAGUCUCUGUGAACCUGCUGUGAUUCUGGGGGCUGCCCAAUUCUCAAAUCGAUCAUUGCUCAAUUAAACUUUAAAUUUAAUUCA